GUCUUCUUGCCUCUCCAGCGCCCGGGGUAGCCCAGGCCCGGGAGAGAGCAGCGGAGAUUCGAGCCUCGGAGGGUGGUUGCCGGCUUUCGAGCAGGCUUGGAGACUCUGCCUGCGUCCUCCACUUCGUCCCGGCCCUUGUCCUGUGGCAGGUGCUCCGCUCAAGAUGAAUCUCAACUUCACCUCUCCUCUACACCCGGCGUCUUCUCAGAGGCCCACAUCCUUCUUCAUCGAGGACAUCCUGCUGCACAAGCCCAAGCCGCUGAGAGAGGUGGCCCCAGACCAUUUCGCCAGCUCUCUGGCCUCUCGGGUGCCUCUGCUAGACUAUGGCUACCCCCUCAUGCCCACACCCACCCUCUUGGCUCCUCACGCCCAUCACCCUCUGCAUAAGGGAGACCACCAUCAUCCUUAUUUCCUCACCACCUCGGGGAUGCCAGUCCCAGCGCUGUUCCCGCACCCGCAGCACGCGGAGCUGCCGGGGAAGCACUGCCGCCGCCGCAAAGCCCGCACGGUUUUCUCUGACUCGCAGCUCUCGGGCUUGGAGAAGAGGUUCGAGAUCCAGCGCUACCUGUCCACGCCAGAACGAGUGGAGCUGGCCACGGCCCUCAGCCUGUCCGAGACGCAGGUGAAAACGUGGUUCCAGAACCGGCGGAUGAAGCAUAAAAAGCAACUGCGGAAAAGCCAAGACGAACCCAAAGCACCAGACGGGCCAGAAAGCCCCGAGGGCAGCCCCCGCGGUUCAGAGGCCGCCACCGCCGCCGAGGCUCGGCUGAGCCUGCCCGCCGGUCCCUUCGUGCUGACCGAGCCAGAGGACGAGGUGGACAUUGGAGACGAGGGGGAGCUGGGCUCAGGGCCGCACGUGCUCUGAGCCGCCAGGCUGGGGAGGGUAGUAGGCAGGGGAGGAGACUGCGGGGCCGAGCGCGGUUCCCUCCUGGACCGGAAGACUC